AGCGCGCGGGAGCGCACGGCGGGGCGCGGCCGACGCUGGGACGCGGCGCACGGAGGGACGCGGCCGGCGCCCAUGGCGUUCGCGCUGCUGCGGCCCGUCGGCGCGCACGUGCUGUACCCGGACGUGCGGCUGCUGAGCGAGGACGAGGAGAACCGCAGCGAGAGCGACGCGUCGGACCAGUCGUUCGGCUGCUGCGAGGGCCCGGAGGCGGCGCGGCGCGGCCCGGGCCCCGGGGGCGGGCGGCGGGCGGGCGGCGGCGGCGGCGCGGGCCCCGUGGUGGUGGUGCGACAGCGGCAGGCGGCCAACGCGCGGGAGCGGGACCGCACUCAGAGCGUGAACACGGCCUUCACGGCGCUGCGCACGCUCAUCCCCACCGAGCCGGUGGACCGCAAGCUGUCCAAGAUCGAGACCGUGCGCCUGGCGUCCAGCUACAUCGCGCACCUGGCCAACGUGCUGCUGCUGGGCGACUCGGCCGACGACGGGCAGCCGUGCUUCCGUGCCGCGGGCAGUGCCAAGGGCGCCGUCCCCGCCGCCGCCGACGGCGGCCGCCAGCCGCGCUCCAUCUGCACCUUCUGCCUCAGCAACCAGCGCAAGGGGGGUGGCCGUCGUGACCUGGGGGGCAGCUGCUUGAAGGUGAGGGGGGUGGCCCCCCUUCGAGGGCCACGGAGAUGAGCCUGGACCCUGGAGAAGGAGGCCAGGAGCCAGCCACUGGCUGGACAGGGAAGAAGACCCCAGGAGCCAAGCCCACCCCUUCUUUGUGUAGGGACCGGGGGACCAUGGCCUGUUCCGGGACACUCUGGGCAGGGCCCUCGGGACAUCUCCACCCGAUCCUGGAGAGCUGUGAGGAUCCAUUCAGCCUGCCCAGCUCUGGCUGGUCAGAGACAAGGCAGAACUUUUGGAAAAACAAAGACUGUUGGUGACAGGGUGUGUGUGUAUCUGUGCGUGAGUGUGAGUGUGUGUGAGAGAGAAUUGGUGAGUUUAAAAUAAAAGCUAUUUUUAAAUAAAA